AUGAGAGACGGCUUCUCAUCAUGGCGGACCCUAGAGAUAAGGCGCUUCAGGACUACCGCAAGAAGUUGCUUGAACACAAGGAGAUCGACGGCCGUCUUAAGGAGUUAAGGGAACAAUUAAAAGAACUUACCAAGCAGUAUGAAAAGUCUGAAAAUGAUCUGAAGGCCCUACAGAGUGUUGGGCAGAUCGUGGGUGAAGUGCUUAAACAGUUAACUGAAGAAAAAUUCAUUGUUAAAGCUACCAAUGGACCAAGAUAUGUUGUGGGUUGUCGUCGACAGGGCUCUGUGGAUGCCGAAAGUUGGCAUUUCUAAGAUAUUUCAGGUUGCAUGAGGACAAGACUGUAUUUGAAGACUAAAAAACAUUAGAAAAGCCGAAGUAUAUAUAAGUUGAGUAUCCCUUAUCCAAAAUGCUUGAGCCAGAAAUGUGUUUUAGAUUUUGGCUUUUUUUUUUUCAGGUUUUAGAAUAUUUGUGUUGUACUGGUUGAGCAUCCCUAAUUAAAAAAAAUCAAAAGUUUGAAAUGCUCCGAUGAGCAUUUUCUUUGAGCAUCAUGUCAGCAUUCAAAAAAUUUCACAUUGUGGAGCAUUUUGGAUUUUCAGAUUAAGAAUACUCAGCCUGUAUUUCCUAUAGAUGUAAACAUUGAAAUAGCUUCAUAUUGAUUUCUCCUCUUAUUUUUUCAAGUAACCUCACUUCUUAGCCGUUUUUUCCUUAAUUGUUAUAUUAAUCCUAGUGUUUUGCCUAUCUUCCUAAAUUUGAAGCUCUUUGUAAAAUCCUGUGACAAGUGGUCAGUAAUUUAUAUGAUUCCGAAAUUGUAUUGGCACGCAGUUUUUUAAACUAUUAAAAAGUAACUUGGGUCGGGCGGGGUGGCUCAUGCCUGUAAUCCCAGCACUUUGGGAGGCUGAGGUGGGCAGAUCACGAGGUCAGGAGAUCAAGACCAGCCUGACCAACAUGGUGAAACCCCGUCUUUACUAAAAAAUACAAAAAAAAAUUAGCCGGGCAUGGUGGCACACACCUGUAAUCCCAGCUACUUGAGGCUGAGGCAGGAGAAUUGCCUAAACCAGGGAGGCAGAGGUUGCUGUGAGCCAAGAUGGCGCCACUGCACUCCAGCCUGGGCGACAGAGUGAGACUCCGUACUCCAUCUCAAAAAAAAAAGUAACUUUAUCUUUGAAAAGUAACAACAUCCUGAGAGUGAGGCAGAUCUAGUAGAUUCUAAUUUUAGCCAGAUAAGCCAAGAAAUUAUUUAGUAUGAUUCAACCUAAUGUGUAAUGUGUUCAGCAUGUGCCUGUCAUGUAGCAAAGGCAUGAGUGAUGGUUGCUGGGUUUUGGGGCUUUAAAUUUAAAGCAUUUUAAUAAAAAUCUCUAAGGGGAAACCGUGCAUUUUUCUCUACUCUCAUGAGCAUUUAACACAUUCUUCCCAGAAGCUGUACAUUUCAAAAUAAAUCUGAUGAGCACACCUUUAAAAUGCUUCCCUUUCCUUUCCCUAAAAUGUUCACUAAGGGAUUUUUCUAUAAAUGCUUUGGUAGCAAUUCCCAAAGUCACUGUACCAUUGCUGCCUCAAGCUUUGUGUGUUAGUCAUUUCACAUUUUACACUGAGAUUACACAAAGGGGCAUGCUUUUAAGGAGCAGGUGGAAAUCACUUUGAAUUACUUAUUUUAUAAGCCAUUUUGUUAGCAUAGAGUUUAUAAUCUGAUAUUUGUGUUCUCUCUGGAGGGUAAAAAUGAGUGUUUGGCUUCUAAAUAUUAAACUCUCGUUAGAGUGUUAUUCCGUUUUUAAGUGUUGAUGUAAUAUCUUUUGUUUUACAAAACUAGCUUGACAAAAGUAAGCUGAAGCCAGGAACAAGAGUUGCUUUGGAUAUGACUACACUAACUAUCAUGAGAUAUUUGCCGAGAGAGGUGGAUCCACUGGUUUAUAACAUGUCUCAUGAGGACCCUGGGAAUGUUUCUUAUUCUGAGAUUGGAGGGCUAUCAGAACAGAUCCGGGAAUUAAGAGAGGUGAUAGAAUUACCUCUUACAAACCCAGAGUUAUUUCAGCGUGUAGGAAUAAUACCUCCAAAAGGCUGUUUGUUAUAUGGACCACCAGGUACGGGAAAAACACUCUUGGCACGAGCCGUUGCUAGCCAGCUGGACUGCAAUUUCUUAAAGGUUGUAUCUAGUUCUAUUGUAGACAAGUACAUUGGUGAAAGUGCUCGUUUGAUCAGAGAAAUGUUUAAUUAUGCUAGAGAUCAUCAACCAUGCAUCAUUUUUAUGGAUGAAAUAGAUGCUAUUGGUGGUCGUCGGUUUUCUGAGGGUACUUCAGCUGACAGAGAGAUUCAGAGAACGUUAAUGGAGUUACUGAAUCAAAUGGAUGGAUUUGAUACUCUGCAUAGAGUUAAAAUGAUCAUGGCUACAAACAGACCAGAUACACUGGAUCCUGCUUUGCUGCGUCCAGGAAGAUUAGAUAGAAAAAUACAUAUUGAUUUGCCAAAUGAACAAGCAAGAUUAGACAUACUGAAAAUCCAUGCAGGUCCCAUUACAAAGCAUGGUGAAAUAGAUUAUGAAGCAAUUGUGAAGCUUUCGGAUGGCUUUAAUGGAGCAGAUCUGAGAAAUGUUUGUACUGAAGCAGGUAUGUUCGCAAUUCGUGCUGAUCAUGAUUUUGUAGUACAGGAAGACUUCAUGAAAGCAGUCAGAAAAGUGGCUGAUUCUAAGAAGCUGGAGUCUAAAUUGGACUACAAACCUGUGUAAUUUACUGUAAGAUUUUUGAUGGCUGCAUGACAGAUGUUGGCUUAUUGUAAAAAUAAAGUUAAAGAAAAUAAUGUAUGUAUUGGUAAUGAUGUCAUUAAAAGUAUAUGAAUAAAAAUAUGAGUAACAUCAUAAAAAUUAGUAAUUCAACUUUUAAGAUACAGAAGAAAUUUGUAUGUUUGUUAAAGUUGCAUUUAUUGCAGCAAGUUACAAAGGGAAAGUGUUGAAGCUUUUCAUAUUUGCUGCGUGAGCAUUUUGUAAAAUAUUGAAAGUGGUUUGAGAUAGUGGUAUAAGAAAGCAUUUCUUAUGACUUAUUUUGUAUCAUUUGUUUUCCUCAUCUAAAAAGUUGAAUAAAAUCUGUUUGAUUCAGUUCUCCUACAUAUAUAUUCUUGUCUUUUCUGAGUAUAUUUACUGUGGUCCUUUAGGUUCUUUAGCAAGUAAACUAUUUGAUAACCCAGAUGGAUUGUGGAUUUUUGAAUAUUAUUUUAAAAUAGUACACAUACUUAAUGUUCAUAAGAUCAUCUUCUUAAAUAAAACAUGGAUGUGUGGGUAUGUCUGUACUCCUCCUUUCAGAAAGUGUUUACAUAUUCUUCAUCUACUGUGAUUAAGCUCAUUGUUGGUUAAUUGAAAAUAUACAUGCACAUCCAUAACUUUUUAAAGAGUAUGAUUCAACGUAAUAUUUGCUAAUAUGUGACUGGGUUUUCUUGGUUUAUGUAAGACGAUAGGUCCCUGUUGAGGAUGUGGAGGUCUGGACCCUCUUCCAGGAAAAAUUCUAACAUACAAUUUUGCGUAUACUAUAAUUUCAGGAAAUUUAUUGUUUCCCAAGCUCAUCCAAGGACUCUUUAGGUAUGUAUGGAUACCUGGCUAAGAGUGUAUGAUGUAGGGGAUGUAGGAGUGUCAGAAAUGUUCAAAACAUGAUUUCUGUUACCUAUACAUGAUUCUUAUAUCAUCUGGCAAUAAAAGCUAUAACAAAGUA